GUAUUAGCAACCUGGAAGAGAGGGCGCCCAGGUGGGCACUCGCAACUUCUCACGUAUCUGCGCGUUCUCUUCGCUCCCACUGGCGUGAGCCUGCGCUUUCCGCCUUCCUUCCCUCACAAGCCCCCUUGGCAACCGUCGCCGUUGAGACGGAGGGAGACGCCCCCACGGAUUCGCCCCGCCGCGCCUCUCCGCGCGUAGAUUGGCCGGAGCGAGGCGAACGGGCCCGGCCUUGGUAGCCGCCGACCGAGCGCUGGCUGUCCUGGAACCUAGGCGGCGGGAGCCCGGGGCGCCUCGCGGCACGGAAGAGCGGCGAGAUGCUCAACCGCAAGACCAGCCACUUUUUGGGAAUGAGGGUGCAGUCGGAGCUUGAACAUCUCUCCGAGCUGCGGCGGGAAGCGGGGAAGGAUCGCAGCUCAGUGCAUGGGUCGGCCGCGCGGACGCGUGCGAGUGUGCGGACUCAGUGGACGACGGCGGCGGCGGCGAAAGCGGAUGAAGACCCCGGAGCCAACUUGUUUCCGUCCUUGAGAUGAGAUGGCAAGUUACAGCGGCUUCUCCGGCCUGCUGGAGAUUCGCUACGGGCCAGGACACCGCAGCUGCCUUCCCCAAUUCGCUUUCUUUCCGCAGCCGCCGCUGCCCCGACCCCGGAUCUGCAUGUGGAAGUACCUGGACGUCCAUUCCAUGCACCAGCUGGAGAAGACCACCAAUGCUGAGAUGAGGGAGGUGCUGGCUGAGCUGCUGGAGCUAGGGUGUCCUGAGCAGAGCCUGAGGGACGCCAUCACCCUGGACCUCUUCUGCCACGCGCUCAUUUUCUGCCGCCAGCAGGGCUUCUCACUGGAGCAGACGUCAGCGGCUUGUGCCCUGCUCCAGGAUCUUCACAAGGCUUGUAUUGCAACCCCCUUGGGCAACGUGGAGGAGUGCUACCGCUACUUCACCAGUGUCCUUUUUUGCCAUGGAGUCAGGGUCAGUUCCCCUGGAACAUUCUGGAAACUUUACCCAUCCCCAGACAAGGUCUCACCCAGUCUCUCUCACAUUCAUCACCCUUAUCUUCUUGUGAAGACCCCAGUGGGCUCUCCUUGCUCCUGUUGCUGGGCUUUUGGAGGCAAAGCCAGGGCUCCGGAAGGUAGUCAGGGUUCUAAUUCCGAGUCACCACCACAGCGGCCUCCUUUCAGCAUCGACCUCUUCAAAGAGGAACAGCUGCUGGCCUUGGAAGACUACGUGGUCAACACUUACUUCCGCCACUUCAAGCUCUAUAAAUACGUCUUCACACCCCAGGUGCGGCUGGAUCUGUCUUUGACUUACAUGGGGCUACAGCCACCCAAACUGUGGCCAGAGAGUGAGACGGAGAAAGAAGAAAGCAAGGAGAUGGAGGAGCAGGCAGUUACCCCGCAGAAAGAGGAACUAGAGACAGUGGCCCCACCAGAGCCAGAGCCAAGCCACAUCCACGUCCUCCGAGCCUACAUCAAGACCCAAGUGAACAAAGAGCUGGAGCAGCUCCAGGGGCUGGUGGAGGAGCGGCUCAAGGCCAGCGAGGAAAGGCUCAGCAGCAAGUUGACUGCACUAGAGCGGCCCUUCCAGCUACCUCCGGGUAAAGGCAAGAGCAAGACCAAGUGACCCCCAACAUUUUCCCCAAUAAAGGUCUGGGCCAGAAUGGCACCAUCCCUGCA